AACUUCAACAUGGCCGAAGCAAGUAGCGCCAAUCUAGGCAGCGGCUGUGAGGAAAAAAGGCAUGAGGGGUCGUCUUCGGAAUCUGUGCCACCCGGCACUACCAUUUCGAGGGUGAAGCUCCUCGACACCAUGGUGGACACUUUUCUUCAGAAGCUGGUCGCCGCCGGCAGCUCUCCACUCCUUCAUUGGGACGGAAGUGCUGGUCCCCGCCUGCCCUCUGGUGGACAGUCUGUGAAACAGGCCUUCAGUUGGGCGGCGUGCAGGUUACCACAGGGGAGGAAGGAGGAAAUCUCUGACAUCAAAGAGGAGGGGAACCUAGAAGCUGUCUUGAAUGCCUUGGAUAAAAUUGUGGAAGAAGGCAAAGUCCGCAAAGAGCCAGCCUGGCGCCCCAGCGGGAUCCCAGAGAAGGAUCUGCACAGUGUUAUGGCACCCUACUUCCUGCAGCAACGGGACACCCUGCGGCGCCAUGUGCAGAAACAGGAGGCCGAGAACCAGCAGCUGGCAGAUGCCGUCCUGGCAGGGCGGAGGCAGGUGGAGGAGCUGCAGCUACAGGUCCAGGCCCAGCAGCAGGCCUGGCAGGCUCUACACAGAGAACAGAGGGAGCUGGUUGCUGUGCUGAGGGAGCCUGAGUGAGGAGACCGCCAGCCCCAGAAGCAGAGGGCAGUCAAGGUCAAGAGCCUGUGGUCCAGCAUGCCUGGCCUGGGCGGGCUACCUCUGAGAACGGCUGAAAUGGUGCCCAGUCCAUCAGCAGUGAUGGAAUUUGCUGGAGGACUAGGCCAGAGCAAGCCUCACUGCCACUGUGCCUUUGGGGCACCCUUGGGGUUGGACAUACACCCCCUUUAGAUUCCUCUGUUUCUUCUACCUGGAUAAUUCUUGGCCAUGUUCUCUCUUCUCUAGGUUCAGGUCAGCUCUGCCCCUCCGCCCCCCUCCUGCUGGUUCCCCAGCCCUUUUCCCUGGCCCUGGCUUGGAGAAUCUGUUUUCAAUCUCCACUGAUUGCCCCCUUGCUGGCCAGCCCAGGGGCCUUUACCAUGUUCUCUCCACAUCCGUAAAUAAACUUCCUUCACUACACUGUAA